GCAUACACUUCUUGGCUGUGUGCGCUCAGCAGGACGUGGGAGGCUCCGGCUUCAAGAUCAAAGGAAAUGUUUCCCUUUGUCCCGUUUCACACUAAACGGGUUGGGGAGGAACCAGGGGAGAUGUCAACCGUCUGCCGGUGACUGGGAAGUUUUCUGCAAGUCCUCCACAGCAUAGGCCAGCAGGCCACUUUUCACUAACAGAAGUCACAAGCCAAGUGAGACACUCAUCCAAGAGGAAGGAUGGCCAGUAUCUUUUCUAAGUUGCUAACUGGCCGCAAUGCUUCUCUGCUGUUUGCUACCAUGGGCACCAGUGUCCUGACCACCGGGUACCUGCUGAACCGGCAGAAAGUGUGUGCCGAGGUCCGGGAGCAGCCUAGGCUAUUUCCUCCAAGCGCAGACUACCCAGACCUGCGCAAGCACAACAACUGCAUGGCCGAGUGCCUCACCCCCGCCAUUUAUGCCAAGCUUCGCAACAAGGUGACACCCAACGGCUACACGCUGGACCAGUGCAUCCAGACUGGAGUGGACAACCCUGGCCACCCCUUCAUAAAGACUGUGGGCAUGGUGGCUGGUGACGAGGAGUCCUAUGAGGUGUUUGCUGACCUUUUUGACCCCGUCAUCAAACUAAGACACAACGGCUAUGACCCCAGGGUGAUGAAGCACACAACGGAUCUGGAUGCAUCAAAGAUCACCCAAGGGCAGUUCGACGAGCAUUACGUGCUGUCUUCUCGGGUGCGCACUGGCCGCAGCAUCCGUGGGCUGAGCCUGCCUCCAGCCUGCACCCGGGCCGAGCGAAGGGAGGUAGAGAACGUGGCCAUCACUGCCCUGGAGGGCCUCAAGGGGGACCUGGCUGGCCGCUACUACAAGCUGUCCGAGAUGACGGAGCAGGACCAGCAGCGGCUCAUCGAUGACCACUUUCUGUUUGAUAAGCCAGUGUCCCCUUUAUUAACAUGUGCUGGGAUGGCCCGUGACUGGCCAGAUGCCAGGGGAAUCUGGCAUAAUUAUGAUAAGACAUUUCUCAUCUGGAUAAAUGAGGAGGAUCACACCAGGGUAAUCUCAAUGGAAAAAGGAGGCAAUAUGAAACGAGUAUUUGAGCGAUUCUGUCGUGGACUAAAAGAAGUAGAACGGUUAAUCCAAGAACGAGGCUGGGAGUUCAUGUGGAAUGAGCGCCUAGGAUACAUUUUGACCUGUCCUUCGAACCUUGGAACAGGACUACGAGCUGGUGUCCACGUUAGGAUCCCAAAGCUCAGCAAGGACCCACGCUUUUCUAAGAUCCUGGAAAACCUAAGACUCCAGAAGCGUGGCACAGGUGGUGUGGACACUGCCGCGGUCGCAGAUGUGUACGACAUUUCCAACAUAGAUAGAAUUGGUCGAUCAGAGGUUGAGCUUGUUCAGAUAGUCAUCGAUGGAGUCAAUUACCUGGUGGAUUGUGAAAAGAAGUUGGAGAGAGGCCAAGAUAUUAAGGUGCCACCCCCUCUGCCUCAGUUUGGCAAAAAGUAAACUUUCCCUUUCCCAAUUUAUAAAUAAUCUGUCUGCUGGUACGACAGACAUAAAUCUCUACUCUGAGAGUUUUUAUACACUUGGAAAAAUAUAAAAUUGUAGAUCCUGCCUAUCUUUACAAUAAAACUCUCCUUAAUAUA